GAGACAGAGAAAGCGCUUCGGCGGCUGCAGCUCGGGCGGCGGCCGCGGGGGACAAAGGGCGGGCGGAUCGGCGGGGAGGGGGCGGGGCGCGGCCAGGCCAAGCCCGGGGGCUCCGCAUGCUGCAGCUGCCCCCGGGCGCCCCCGCCGCCGCCCUCGCCGCGGAGCCGCGCGGAGCGGAGCCGGCGAGCUAACCCGAGCCAGCCGGCGGGCGUCCCGGAGGCGGUGGCGCAGGGAGGGGCCCGACGCUCGCACGUGGCCCCGGCGGCCGCCAUGGCGGACAGCGGCACCGCGGGGGGCGCGGCGUUGGCGGCCCCGGCCCCCGGGCCGGGCAGUGGCGGCCCAGGACCACGCGUCUACUUUCAGAGCCCCCCCGGGGCCGCAGGAGAGGGCCCGGGCGGGGCGGACGAUGAGGGCCCAGUGAGGCGCCAAGGGAAGGUCACCGUCAAGUAUGACCGCAAGGAGCUACGGAAGCGCCUCAACCUAGAGGAGUGGAUCCUGGAGCAGCUCACGCGCCUCUACGACUGCCAGGAAGAGGAGAUCCCAGAACUGGAGAUUGACGUGGAUGAGCUCCUGGACAUGGAGAGUGACGAUGCCCGGGCUGCCAGGGUCAAGGAGCUGCUGGUUGACUGUUACAAACCCACAGAGGCCUUCAUUUCUGGCCUGCUGGACAAGAUCCGGGGCAUGCAGAAGCUGAGCACACCCCAGAAGAAGUGACGGUCCCCGACCCAGGAGAACGGUGGCUCCCACAGGACAAUCGCUGCCCCCCAACCUCGUAGCAACAGCAAUACCGGGGGACCCUGCGGCCAGGCCUGGUGCCAUGAGCAGGGCUCCUCGUGCCCCUGGCCCAGGGGUCUCUUCCCCUGCCCCCUCAGUUUUCCACUUUUGGGGUUUUUUAUUGUUAUUAAACUGAUGGGACUUUUUGUGUUUUUAUAUUGACUCUGCGGCGCGGGCCCUUUAAUAAAGCUAGGAUACGCCUUUGGUGCAGCUAA